GUUACAAGCAUGACUUCUAUUAAACCUAUAGGUAAGAUUAUUUUCUACUUUUAAUGCAGUAUGUUUGUUUUUAUCCUGACUUUUGAUUCAUUAGGCCAUGUGGUUUAAGUCUAAACUAAGUUACUCUGAUAUUCGGAAUUUCACCUUUAAUAAUUUUCUGGAAAUUUUCUUUUAAAGGUGAUAUUAGAAAUCUCCAUUUCAGUCUCAGCAUUUCACUAGCAUUACAUGAUGCUCUUGUCUUUUGCAAUUUAAUAUUCAAAUUACAUAGAUAUUUUUUAUUACUGCAUGUGAAGUCCUUCCUCAACUUAUAAAGCAGUUAGAACAUACUAAUACUUUAAUACUUCUAUAAGUGACGAGCUGGCAACUGAAAAAUGUUCAUCUAUUAUACAUAUAUAAGCAUAAGUGUGUGUAUGCCUAAAUGUAUGUAUGUAUACAUUUCCAUGAUUAGUAUUCCCUAAAGAUUAAAGUGAUAAAAUAAAUGUUGCCUGGUUUUACAUUGGUAACUAAUGUUAUGAGAUAGUUCAUAGGUCAAUAGAAUGAAAUUUUAUGUUUUAUUUAAUCUAAAAUAAUUCUGUUGAUUGCCACCUACAUAUGUUCACUGUUCAUUUUCUAUUGUGUCUAGACAUUAUUUUGCUCUUAAUGUAAUAUCAGGUUAAAAUUAUUCAACUUGUGCAAAGAUUUUGAGAAAAAUAUGUAAAAUUAGAUUUUGAUCAAGGAUAAAUGUAUCUUUUUUUUUCUUUGAAGAAAAGAGUAUAGGCCCUUCAGUCAGUCAGUUUGGGUUCCAGCCCUUGUUCUGCCAAGUACUAGCUGUGUGAACUCAGCUAGUCAUCUAAAGAGCCUAGUAAGGAGAGAUGAUUAUUCAGCAAGGUAAUACAUGUGAAAUACUUAGCUCCACACCUGGCAGGUAGUAAGCUCCUACUAUGUGUUGACUAUGUUAUUGUAUGAUCAUCUUCAUUGUUCUUUGCUCUUCAAGUCUUUGUUCACCCAUUCAAUCUAGAAUUACAAUGCAAGUUAUACUAAAAUGCUUCUUUUCAUUUGCUGAACUGUUAAAAAAAAUCGCUUAGUUUUCUUUUAAAUGGUAUCUACUACUAUAAGAUAUUCUUGUAUCUGCAUAUAGCCUUACAUUUUAAAGUUUAAAUCUACUAUCUGAUCUUCAGCUUAAAGGUAGGUAGACUUUAUAGGUUAUCCCAUUUAACAAGAAAGGACAACAGGAAUACAAUGAUUAUUACGUCUUGCCUAGUUCACAAAUCCUAUUGCUAAUAAAGGAAUCACACGGGCCAUGUGAUUCCUCUUCCAGAACUCUUGUUACCCAUCUGUCAUUUGCUUCUCAAAUAUGUUGCAAUAUUUGUUACUCAACUUACUGUACUCUUCCUCUUUUAUUUCACAAGUGUUACAUUCCAUGAAUCAGCUUGUCCAAAAGUACUGUUAAAAGGAUUUUUUUUAACUAUACAAAUGCUAAAAGAAAGUUUAUUUUUUUUUUAGUAUGCUCAAAGUGGAUAAAGGCUUUCAAAGCAUGAUACAAUCCUCAAAAGGAAAUGACUCAAAGUUUAUGGAAUAAAAAUGUAAACAUUUCUAUCUUGUAUGCUAAGCUACUCAGGAACUGUUGUCUAUGGGAUUGAACACUUAACAGCUGUCUCUGGGAAUGUAAAUUUGAUUCUUUGGACUGCUCAUGGGACUCUGUGACAUUUUCCUCUCCAGUGACAGCAGAUUUGAAUGGCAUUAGGCUACUGAUUAAAUAAUACCCAAAUAGCUUUCCAAUGAUUAGACGAAUUGAUUCUUUCUGUGACUCAUCAGUUCAUUUCCUGUAAAAUUCAUGUCUUGCUGUUGAUUUGUGAAUAAGAACCAGAGCUUGUAGAAACCACUUUAAUCAUAUCCAGGAGUUUGCAAGAAACAGGUGCUUAACACUAAUUCACCUCCUGAACAAGAAAAAUGGGCUGUGACCGGAACUGUGGGCUCAUCGCUGGGGCUGUCAUUGGUGCUGUCCUGGCUGUGUUUGGAGGUAUUCUAAUGCCAGUUGGAGACCUGCUUAUCCAGAAGACAAUUAAAAAGCAAGUUGUCCUCGAAGAAGGUACAAUUGCUUUUAAAAAUUGGGUUAAAACAGGCACAGAAGUUUACAGACAGUUUUGGAUCUUUGAUGUGCAAAAUCCACAGGAAGUGAUGAUGAACAGCAGCAACAUUCAAGUUAAGCAAAGAGGUCCUUAUACGUACAGAGUUCGUUUUCUAGCCAAGGAAAAUGUAACCCAGGACGCUGAGGACAACACAGUCUCUUUCCUGCAGCCCAAUGGUGCCAUCUUCGAACCUUCACUAUCAGUUGGAACAGAGGCUGACAACUUCACAGUUCUCAAUCUGGCUGUGGCAGCUGCAUCCCAUAUCUAUCAAAAUCAAUUUGUUCAAAUGAUCCUCAAUUCACUUAUUAACAAGUCAAAAUCUUCUAUGUUCCAAGUCAGAACUUUGAGAGAACUGUUAUGGGGCUAUAGGGAUCCAUUUUUGAGUUUGGUUCCGUACCCUGUUACUACCACAGUUGGUCUGUUUUAUCCUUACAACAAUACUGCAGAUGGAGUUUAUAAAGUUUUCAAUGGAAAAGAUAACAUAAGUAAAGUUGCCAUAAUCGACACAUAUAAAGGUAAAAGGAAUCUGUCCUAUUGGGAAAGUCACUGCGACAUGAUUAAUGGUACAGAUGCAGCCUCAUUUCCACCUUUUGUUGAGAAAAGCCAGGUAUUGCAGUUCUUUUCUUCUGAUAUUUGCAGGUCAAUCUAUGCUGUAUUUGAAUCCGACGUUAAUCUGAAAGGAAUCCCUGUGUAUAGAUUUGUUCUUCCAUCCAAGGCCUUUGCCUCUCCAGUUGAAAACCCAGACAACUAUUGUUUCUGCACAGAAAAAAUUAUCUCAAAAAAUUGUACAUCAUAUGGUGUGCUAGACAUCAGCAAAUGCAAAGAAGGGAGACCUGUGUACAUUUCACUUCCUCAUUUUCUGUAUGCAAGUCCUGAUGUUUCAGAACCUAUUGAUGGAUUAAACCCAAAUGAAGAAGAACAUAGGACAUACUUGGAUAUUGAACCUAUAACUGGAUUCACUUUACAAUUUGCAAAACGGCUGCAGGUCAACCUAUUGGUCAAGCCAUCAGAAAAAAUUCAAGUAUUAAAGAAUCUGAAGAGGAACUAUAUUGUGCCUAUUCUUUGGCUUAAUGAGACUGGGACCAUUGGUGAUGAGAAGGCAAACAUGUUCAGAAGUCAAGUAACUGGAAAAAUAAACCUCCUUGGCCUGAUAGAAAUGAUCUUACUCAGUGUUGGUGUGGUGAUGUUUGUUGCUUUUAUGAUUUCAUAUUGUGCAUGCAGAUCGAAAACAAUAAAAUAAACCUGGCUCAAGCACAAACCAAUUUGUGUUGUUCUGAUUCAAUAAUUGGUUUCUGGGUGGCCAAUUCAGAAGAAGAGUGUACAUGCUCAACAAAUCCUAGGCCCUGCAUUCCUGUCAUCCUCAUCCGGGGGAAACACCAUCAUCCCAGUAGCUGCCCUAUUCAACUGCAACAGUCUCCAGGACCAUCAGUAUACUGCAUUUCAUGUGCACCAAAUAUUUUGAAAGACAUUUAUAAAUAAUUGGCUUAUGACUCAUAUUUCUCUAUGAAUACCUUCAUACAGCAGGUAUAACUCUUUUCUUUAUGGGCUUAAAUAUUUUGUCACUGAUCCUGCAAAUGGACAUCAUUUUAGCACACUAGCGGUUUAUAUUUUAAGGACCUUCAUUCUCUGUUCUGCACCUCUUCUGGAAAUUGAGUAAAUUUUGCUUUUUUUUUUUUACUCAGUUGCAACUUACGCUUGGCAUCUUCAGAAUGCUUUUCUAGCAUUAAGAGAUGUAAAUGAUAAAGGAAUUAUUGUAUGAAAUAUUACAAAGCGUAGACUAUGCAUUGUUAUUCAUUAUAAUAUUUUUUGCUGUCAUAAUCGCCUCAUAAAGACAGGUUUCAACCAUUAAAAUAUGUUCUUCCUUAAAUUCCUGUGCUUUUUCUAGUUCCUCUUGUGUCAUAAAAUGUUUAUCCUAAUUUUCUCUCUGAAGUAUAUUUUAUCUGAAUCCACAUUUCUUUAUAAAUCCAUAGUCCUUGCUGAAAUAUGCUUUCUAAAUUUCUACCACUUUGUUCUAGGCUAAUUUUUUAAGCUAAUUGGAUGAAGAACAAAAAGACAUUUGGUUUCAUCCUUUACAGCAGUAGGACAAUUGCAAAGGUUUUUCCUUUUUCAUAAGGAGACACAUUAAUAGGUAACUCUGUUUCUUGAGCAGGGGUUCACUUAUUCUGAGAGCAUUAGUUCUCCUAAAAAGCUCCAGCAUAGAAAGGGAAGAUAAACCAAAUUCUAGCUUGUGUUUUACCCACAGAAGGAUACAGGACAAAGGAAUAGUAACUGGCCUGUUUGGAUACUAAAAUCGAAAAUAACUUUUAGCCUCCUCCUUAUGAUAGCCGCCAGAGUAAAUGUUGAGCAUUACUACAGAAAAGCCACAAACCAAGAAUCUACCUGUUUGGAAAGAUCUUUUGCAUCUCUGAAGGUGCUUAAAGCAUACUUAGUGCCUUUCCUUUUAACUGGGAAGAUAAAAGAAGUAUCUGUCCAAGAUAUUAAUAUGUAAGAUAACAUUGUAGACAUGUUCUUCUGAUAAUACAAGGUUUAUUCUAUUUGCAUUAGGAUAUUUGUGGACAUGUCCAUCUAAUAUAAAGGAAAGUUUUUUAAUCAUUGAGGCAUGUAGGGCUGAGUUAUAUAAUGUAGAAACUUCUAAAGAUAAUUGGAUGAGAAUAUACAUAUUGACCUGUAUAUUAUGACUAAUCAUGACUCAGAUCUUAAUACAGGGAUGAUCUCAUAGCAUUUAGAUAUCAGAAAAGGUUUUGACCUAUAUGUCUUUAAUAUUGUUUGAAUACAUGUAUAAUCUUUAUCAUUCCUCAGUGUUUCAUUUCUCAAAUUCUGUAAAAGGAAUAUAAGAGGAAAGACAAUUCAUAUACAAAGACAACGAGAUUAAAAAUAUGCAGUAGGAAAAAUAAUUACUUAAGGGGAGAUUUUUUUUACAUGAAAUCUGGGCUUUGGAUGUGUGUGUGUGUGUGUGUGUGUGUGUGUGUGCACAUAUGCACUGUGGUGGGAGUGGGGCAACUUGGGGAAUAUGUUACAUGUGUGACUUUGUUUUGCCCUGGCGAAGUUAAUGUUGUUCAGAAAGGGUAAAUGUUUGGACACUUGCAAUUGCUCAUGGAUGAAUUUAUAUGUUUUAGUCAUAGAAAAAUUGUACCCUUUGAUAGAAGCACAUUUUCUUUCCAAAGCUGGUUAUUAACCACAGAAUUAUAGCAGGUAUUCAUAACUUAAGUUUGAAAAUCAAUAGCGUCUGCAAAUGGAUUAACAGAUUAGAGAAUCAACAGCAUCGGAAAAUAGGUUAAUGCAUAUUGCUUCUAACAAGUGCAUGAAGAAAUAGAAGAAGCUAUGUAGCUUUCAGUUCUGACAGAAAAGGGUGAAGGAGGGUAUCAUUUCAAGAAAAAAAAUAGCUAUCACGCAAUGGUUAUCUCUGAAAAUAUUUGUAUUAAGAUGUGUAUACAUGGCCAGGCAUGGUGGCUCAUGCCUGUAAUCCCAGCACUUUGGGAGGCAGGUGGAUCACGAGGUCAGGAGAUCAAGACCAUCCUGGCCAACAUGGUGAAACCUCAUCUCUACUAAAAAUACAAAAAUGAGCGGGGUGUGGUGGCCCAUGCCUGUAGUCCCAGCUGCUCGGGAGACUGAAUCUCUUGAGCCUGGGAAGCAGAGGUUGCAGUGAACUGAGAUCGCGUCACUGCACUCCAGCCUGGUGACAGAGCGAGAUUCCAUCUCAAAAAAAAAAAACAGUAUGCACGUACAAAUUUCUUAACCUGUUAUCAAUGUCUGAGCUACAUAAUUAUCUUUCUAGUUGGAGUUUGUUUUAGGUGUGUACCAACUGACAUUUCAGUUUUUCUGUUUGAAGUCCAAUGUAUUAGUGACUCUGUGGCUGCUCUCUUCACCUGCCCCUUGUGGCCUGUCUACAAUUCUAAAUGGAUUUUGAACUCAAUGUCGUCGCUUCUGGUUUCCUGCAUAUACCAAUAGCAUUACCUAUGACUUUUUUUUUCCUGAGCUAUUUUCACUGAGCUGAGCUAAUGAACUAAAACUGAGUUAUGUUUAAUAUUUGUAUCAAAUACAUAAAAGGAAUACUGCUUUUUCCUUUUGUGGCUCAAAGGUAGCUGCAUUUUAAAAUAUUUGUGAAAAUAAAAACUUUUGUUAUUAGAAAAA